CAGGCACCAUGACUCCUGUGAGGAUGCAGCACUCCCUGGCAGGUCAGACCUAUGCCGUGCCCUUCAUCCAGCCAGACCUGCGGCGAGAGGAGGCCGUCCAGCAGAUGGCGGAUGCCCUGCAGUACCUGCAGAAGGUCUCUGGAGACAUCUUCAGCAGGUGGGUGCUGCCACUCACCCCCACCUGAUGAGAGGGCCAUCCCUGUCCUGGGCAAUCCCAGCAACACACCCUCUGGGAGCAGCCCCCUUGGGGAAUCCCGGUCCUGGGGAACCCAUCUGGCUUCCCUGUGUGGGAGGGGCUGAAGUGAGAGCCCAACUUGGAAGCUUUUACUCCUGGGAGUCCGAGAGCUCACUCCCUUCCACCCCACUUAGCCUCCUGGUUUCCUGUGGUGGCUCUGCUCUCACAACUCAUGCUUUUCCUCCCAUUGGAGGGCCUAUUCCUUCACGUUUUCCUGCAGCCAACAAAUAUUUACCCAGCAGUGCUCGUGUGCAAGGCAGUGUGGGAAUCUCUAUAUAUCCAGCCACGGAUAAGGCAACAUACCUCUCCACCUGGAGCGCACAUUCUGGCAGGAGAGAAAGACCUAAAUAAGCAAUAGAUGAUUAGUUCUUCAAUAACAGUUGUGACAAGGUCUAUUGAUAAUAUUUUGUAAUCACUAAUAUUCAUAUAAACCGUGCACAACCAUUGAUUUGAGUGCAUUAACUCACACUUCAUGAGCAGGCACUGCCGUCAUCUCAUUUUAUAGAUGAGGAAACUGAGGCACAGAAGGGCUGAGAGACCUGGCCUAGUGACAGAGCCAGGAUUCAAAGCCAUAGAUCAUGGCCCCGGGUUAUGUAGGUUAUUACUGCAUCUGUUCAGGGGAGAUGGGGUACUGUGAGGCUCGUCAUGGGAAGCCUGGCUUGGUCUCAGGUCAGGGAAGGCAGAUGUGAGGAAAUGACAUUUAUGGUAAAGUCUGAGGGUUGAGUGGGUAGGUUGGGAAGAACAUUCCAGAAAGAAGCACAUGAACUACAGCCUGGAGGUGGAGGACCUAAAAGGAAGCCAGCAUGGCUGGAGCACGGAGUGGCCAUUGAGGGAGGCGAGCUGGAGGGCUGCAGCUUCUUGUAUUGGCAGUGCUGACCUCGCACAGUCCUUGGGCUCCAGUGACUUCACUCAGUGUUUAUCUAACAUGAGUGAGUGAAUGGUGUUUGCUGUUUUUUUGGUAAAGGUCCCAGGGGUUGUCGGGUACACAGGUCCUGUCUUUGGCCAUAAGCAAACUGAAAUGAGGCUUGGUCUCCUUCCCAGGAUCCCACACCAUGUCUCACAUGGUAGACCCCAGUGGGAAGUAUGUGACUGCCUGACUCAGGUGCCUCUCGUGGUCCAAGCCAUCCCUGCCCUGUCCCUUCCCUGGUUGUCGCCAGACCUGGAGCCCCUGCUCCUUCACUUUGCAGCCUCCUCUUCUGUCACCAACUGGGAACCCACCUCUUCCUGAAAGUCCUCCCCCACUGACUCACCGGCUUGCCCCGAGUUUGUCAAGAAUGUCUCAGUAACCAGGGGACACACAGUGAAGUGACUGAGGGGUUACCUUGGAGUUGAUGCCUUGGCUCAGAUCCAGCUCCCCUGUUUUCUUCCUCUGUAACCUUGGGCAACCCAACCCCUCUAAGCCUCGGUGUUCUCAUUUGUGAAGUUGUGGUAAUAAUGGUAGCUUCCUGGUAGAAUUAUUUUAAAUAUUAAAUUAAUCAAAACAUGCAAAGGAAUGGAACAGUGCCUGGCACCUAGGAAGCCUUCAGGAAAUGCUAUCUCUUCCCUGUUGAUAAUCUUGACCCGUACACUGCCUUUGGUUGCCAUUCAUAAACCUGCCACCAAUAGUAACAAAGUGCUGGAUGCACCUUUUGUGCUUAUCUUUGUGCUAAAUGUGCCCGAGGGACACCUAGGGAAGAGGAUGCAGGUCUUUAAGAGCCAUCAGCUCCAGAUUAUGGCCACCCCAUGUCCAGCACUUAGAAUGGAGGCCAAAACCAUUCCCUCGGAAAUUGUGUUUCCUUGCCAAGAUGGGGACUGCGUGGUUGCCCUUCUCUGAGGGCAGCGCUGGAUUUUUGGCGUCUUUCCUUUCCUGUCCUGGUACUUGGCACCUUGUAGACAGUUGCAUGUCCCCUGCCCAGGGAUGGGAUGAGGAGAGGGCAGGAAGGCAUUUCCUGGGUAGUGGAGUGCUGCGUUCAUUGAGUGUGGGUUCUCCAAGCUGCUGGCACAGCGCAGGGAGGGCCAGAUGCCUCUCAGGAGCCUUGGGCCUGAGUCCUGGCUCCCUCACUCCUGGGUUCCAGGUCACUGCAUCUGUCUCUCCACCAUGUGCUCCACCUCGUGCUGGACCUUAAGAGAUACCAAUUAUGUGGCUGCCACUGUGUCCUAGAGGCUGGAAUGGGAACACAUAGGGCGAGAUUGAUUGUUAAUUGCUAGCAUGAACCGCGUGGGCUUCUCAGGGUCUAGAGUGGAGAGAAAUCGGUAAGAAUUGGUGGCACGCCUGUCAGAACUCCCCAGACCAAGCUAAGCAAAAAUUAACCAAUCAGUAGAGCAGCCUUCGGAGUAAGGGCUAAAAUGAUGUCCUCAGGGCCUGGUUUUGCUUUCCUUCCAUGUCAGUUUGCUUCUUUGGGUCUGGCUGCAUUCCCAGACAGGCCAUGCUCUCGUGGUAGCAAGGUGACAUGACACAGGGUCAGGUCCAGCAGGAAAGAAUGCUGUCCUGUGUCCCCGCUUCCUCCAGAAGCCACACUCACCCAUCCCACCUGGCUUGGUCCUCAUGUCUAUCCCAGAAUCCAUUAAUGGGGCCAGGGGACUAUGACACACCACUUGGCUUAGACUGAGGAGCUCUGUGGGCAGCCCCACCUGAAGCUCUGGGACUAAGCCUGCGAGAGAGAUGGAUUCCCCAAGGGAAAUGGGGCCAUUGCUUGAGUAAAAAGGAAAUAGUUGCUGAAGAGGAAAACCACGUGCUUACUCCACAUAGGGCAGACUCCUGGAAGAGGGGGGCAGGGUAGGGAGGUGGAUAUGCAGGUUGCCCUGGCAGGGUCUGGAAAUGGGGGCUGCAGGCUUGGAGGGAGGCCUCAGUGUGGCUUGGAACGUGGUGUAUGGUGGUCUGCCGCGAAGGCCGGCCUGCACAGGGGUGGGAGGGGGGUGCUUCUGCAUGGGAAGCACAGACAGCGCUGCCUCUCCCUUGCACUCAGCUCUUGGGGCAUGAGAGGCUGACUUUCCGUGAGCCUGUGGGCCAGGCCUCUUUGAAUGGGGCUGAGGGAGCUUUGCCCUGGUUCCUUUGUGUCCCCACGGUGCCACGGGAGGCUCCCUGGCAGGGUGUGGGGCAAGGCAGUGAGUGAAGAGUUGGGAUGAGUGAGUUAGGGCCCACGGAUUACUCAAGACAGGACUUCAAGUUGAUUCAGGCGUGUUAGGGAGCUGUGAUUGGAUUUUGAGCAGGGCAGGGAUGGGACAGAAGAGUUUGGGGAAGGUUCCUCAGGCAUCCGUCACGGAAGGGACAAGAAGGGAGAGAGAGUGGAUGCCAGGGACACCCAGAAGCUGUUAUUGUAGUCAGGAUACGACAGGGGUGAGGCUACAGACAGGGGACUUGCAAGCAGGGAGGGCAGGGUGAGACAUUCAGAGGAAACGACGACAGGAAAUGGUGACAGAUAGGGAACGAGGAUGAAGGGAAGGGAGAGCCAGUGACGACUGGCAGUGGAGUGGGGAGCACCGCCACCUCUCCUCCUCCACUUGCCCCUCCUGUGGCACUGGACAAGCUAGUGGGCUUUUCGUUGUCCAUGGGCUUUUUCGGUGGGGAUGUGACCAGCUUUGAACCCGUCCCCUUAAACAUGCUCCUCCUGCACGGAAGAGACAGGGGCAGGGGAGAGACUCUCUCCCCACCACCCAGCUCAGGCCCCAGCACAGCCCGGCCUCUGGCCUCACUGGCGUCUGUGCCCAGUGACGCAGGCAGGUGAGCUCCUGGCAAAUUAGCAUUGCAGGCUGUGCUCUCUCCUCCUGCUCUGCUGCAGCUGGGAGUGUGCAGAGACUGGAGGGGAUGACAGUCACCCUCUGUUUUCUGUGGUGGCUCUGUUUUCUGUGGUGCUGGAUGCACCUCUGUUUUCUGUGGUGGCUCCAAGAGAGUGCACGGUCCCUGCUGAUUGAAAGAAGGAUGAAGGGCAGAAGAGGGGCGGGGAGCUGUGUGCCCUAAGAUCUCAUUGCCUUUUUAUGCCGAUUAACAUGCUUUUAGCCCCUACUGAGCUUAUAGUUAACAGAAGUUUCCAGGUCUUUCUUCACCUGAACUGUGUCUAAAGCAAGUUCUCUCCACCUUCUGUAUUUAUACGCUUGAUUUUUAAAACCUAAAUGUUGGGCUUCACAUUUCUUCCUUGUAAAUUUCAUCUUGGUGAUUGCAGUCUACCCUCUGGCCUUUAAAAAUUGUCUGAGCCUUGAUUCGAUCAUGAAACCAGCUUACCCUUCCCCUGUGUGCUGGCCCCAGUUUUCUAACCAGGUGUUGAAUGAACUGGAUGGACUCUGCCAGAUCCCUCCGUGCAAGGCUGGAAUCAGUCCAUUGUUCAACUGUGCCCUUUGGGGCUGUGGUUCAUUUGGCUCUGAUUUUUCCUAUAUGUUCUCUCCUCCAACCCCCAUAGCUCCAUCUUGUCUACAAGAUUUUGUUAGAAGCCGUCAAAAUCCUGCUGACUCGAGAUGCGCUGUGGUGCAUGUUUUCCCCGGGCACAGCAGGCUAAUAAUCCUGUUACAAAGAGAAAUGCUGUACAUUUCGAGCAGUGCUGGCCCCUGGGACUCACCGUGGCCUUUUCUAAGUGCUUACAGACUCUCUGUUUAAUAAUCCAUUCCAGAAAUUUUCCAGGGCUCAUUGUUGAGCUUGGUGUUCGCAACUUUGAGUGAUCAGCCCUUCUCCUUUGUGGGAGCACCAGGACAGAGCAGCCUUUGUCCCUCCCCAGUCUCAGUUCCCUCCCACUGCCCCUGUGGACCUCGAAUGCAGAGCUUAUGCACCUACCGAAGGUCGUGUCAGCACCCAAGGCAGAACGAGGCUGCCCUGGGAACUAGGGUCAAUUAAGACAGCUUGUGCUGGAGGACCCUUUACAGCAGAUGAAGGCCUCUCCCCAGCCAGAAAAGAUGGAGCACACGCUGGGUGGUGGCCCCGCUUCCUCACUGGAAGGAGAUGGUGCUCUUCUUUUUUCUUUCUGAAUUGUGGCCACCUUCAUACCAGUCUGUCAUGGAACACUUAAGCCGCUUGAGUGCCUGCUGGUACUCCCAGCCCUGCCAUGCCUGAGCCCCCUGCACACAAGGAGCCAGGAGUAAUCAGGGCAGACCCUUUAGGGCACGGGGACUUCUGGAUUGUGAAAUUGGCUCUCUGGGGGCCAAGGCCUUCUAACGUUGGUGGAAGUGGCUUUGGCUUAUUGGGUCGGAUUCUAGGCCAUUCAUUCCAACCUUUAGAGACAUCCCAGCUUUCCCUAGCCCAGAGUCUGCAGCCCCUCCACCAUCCCACAUCCUCCCCCUCCCUUUCCUCAUGAACCCCAGUCGCGCCUCUGCCUUCUCAAACCCCUCCACCAUCCCACACCCUCCUCCUGCCCUUCCUCAUGAACCCCAGUCGCGCCUCUGCCUUCUCAUCCCUGCGCACCACACAGGCUCGCUCGUGCCCGGUGAGUGCUGAGGCUGCUCUGCACGUGGAGUAUGGCCCUGUGGGCAAGGGCUGGGCUCUUGGAGGUAGGGGAGCUACAGGGGCGACUGGGAGGAGGAUGUUGUGUUACACACGCAUCAGAGUUAACUUUGCAGUGAGAGCGGCCUUGCUGCGGCCAAAGAACAUGGAAAAGCAUGAGUGGGGUGAUGUGCCUUAAAGCAUCAGACACUUGGGCCUCGGGCAUCAGGAGCCAGCCACAGGGAUGUCUGGGGAAAUGGCGUUCCAUGAGAUGCAAGCACACAAGAAUGCACUUGGCACAUCUGGGGAACAGCAGGCAGCUGAUAUCACUGGGCCCACCCCGCACCAGGGAGGAUGGAAGCAGGUAGAGCAGAGCCGGAGCCAGGUGCAGGCCAUUGGAGAGAAGGUCUCCUUGGCCCAGGCCAAGAUUGAGAAGAUCAAGGGCAGCAAGAAGGCCAUCAAGGUGUUCUCCAGUGCCAAGUACCCUGCUCCAGGGCGCCUGCAGGAAUAUGGCUCCAUCUUCACGGGCGCCCAGGACCCUGGCCUGCAGAGACGCCCCCGCCACAGGAUCCAGAGCAAGCACCGCCCCCUGGACGAGCGGGCCCUGCAGGAGAAGCUGAAGGACUUUCCUGUGUGCGUGAGCACCAAGCCGGAGCCCGAGGACGAUGCAGAAGAGGGACUUGGGGGUCUUCCCAGCAACAUCAGCUCUGUCAGCUCCUUGCUGCUCUUCAACACCACCGAGAACCUGUACAAGAAGUAUGUCUUCCUGGACCCCCUGGCUGGUGCUGUAACAAAGACCCAUGUGAUGCUGGGGGCAGAGACAGAGGAGAAGCUGUUUGAUGCCCCCUUGUCCAUCAGCAAGAGAGAGCAGCUGGAACAGCAGGUCCCAGAGAACUACUUCUAUGUGCCAGACCUGGGCCAGGUGCCUGAGAUCCAUGUUCCAUCCUACCUGCCUGACCUGCCCGGCAUUGCCAACGACCUCAUGUACAGUGCCGACCUGGGCCCCGGCAUUGCCCCCUCUGCCCCUGGCACCAUUCCAGAACUGCCCACCUUCCACACUGAGGUAGCCGAGCCUCUCAAGGUAGACCUACAAGAUGGGGUACUAACACCACCCCCACCGCCCCCACCACCACCCCCAGCUCCUGAGGUGCUGGCCAGUGCACCCCCACUCCCACCCUCAACCGCGGCCCCUGUAGGCCAAGGCGCCAGGCAGGACGACAGCAGCAGCAGCGCAUCUCCUUCAGUCCAGGGAGCUCCCAGGGAAGUGGUCGACCCCUCCGGUGGCUGGGCCACUCUGCUAGAGUCCAUCCGCCAAGCUGGGGGCAUCGGCAAGGCCAAGCUGCGCAGCAUGAAGGAGCGAAAGCUGGAGAAGCAGCAGCAGAAGGAGCAGGAGCAAGUGAGAGCCACGAGCCAAGGUGGGCACUUGAUGUCGGAUCUCUUCAACAAGCUGGUCAUGAGGCGCAAGGGCAUCUCUGGGAAAGGACCUGGGGCUGGUGAGGGGCCCGGAGGAGCCUUUGUCCGCGUGUCAGACUCCAUCCCUCCUUUGCCGCCACCGCAGCAGCCACAGGCAGAGGAGGACGAGGACGACUGGGAAUCGUAGGGGGCUCCAUGACACCUUCCCCCCCAGACCCAGACUUGGGCCGUUGCUCUGACAUGGACACAGCCAGGACAAGCUGCUCAGACCUGCUUCCCUGGGAGGGGGUGACGGAACCAGCAGUGUGUGGAGACCAGCUUCAAGGAGCGGAAGGCUGGCUUGAGGCCACACAGCUGGGGCGGGGACUUGUCUGCCUGUACUUCAUGGGGGGACGGCUCCACCCAGCCUGCGCCACUGUGUUCUUAAGAGGCUUCCAGAGAAAACGGCACACCAAUCAAUAAAGAACUGAGCAGAAACCAA